AGUGGCGCUGCGCUGAAUGCAACUGCGCGCGCCCGCCGGGUGAGCCAGCGAUCUGAGCCAGGCGGGGGCGGCCCGACCUUUCCCGCCCAGCCUGGGUCAGAGGAAGCCGAAAGCGGCCUCAGCAAGGUGAGGCGCCCGAGGCUGCAGAAGACCGAGCAGAACUUUGCAGAGUUCGGGAUGUGCUGGGCUAGGUCGCUGAGGACUUGACUGGCUUCCUCCCUCCUUCCCUCCACCUACCUUCUCCCUCCCCCUCCACCAUCCAGUGGGUUCGUUCCGGGCCUCCAGCUAUCAGCUCCCGAUCUCGUGUUUGAGGGUAGCGACCCCGAUUUCUGUUUGCAUGCACAGCCAGCAGCCCUAGCGCCAGAUCCUAAAGCUGGAUAUCUUUUAACUGGGCUACCAGCCCGGGCCUCAAAGUUUUGAGUGAGGGCCGCCAGGCUCAGGCCCCAGCGAAGCCCCGAGCGCCAUGGCCGACCCGCAGGCUGGCUCCGCGGCCGGGGACUGGGAGAUCGAUGUCGAGAGCCUGGAGCUGGAAGAGGACGUCUGCGGGGCGCCGCGGUCCACGCCCCCCGGGCCCAGCCCGCCGCCGGCGGACGGGGACUGCGAGGACGACGAAGAUGACGACGGGGUGGACGAAGACGCGGAAGAAGAGGGCGACGGCGAGGAGGCAGGCGCGUCCCCCGGGAUGCCCGGCCAGCCGGAGCAGCGGGGGGGACCGCAGCCGAGGCCGCCGCUCGCGCCUCAGGCCUCACCCGCCGGCACCGGUCCCCGAGAGCGCUGCACUCCCGCGGGCGGCGGCGCGGAGCCGCGCAAGCUGAGCCGCACGCCCAAGUGCGCGCGCUGCCGCAACCACGGCGUGGUGUCCUGCCUGAAGGGCCACAAGCGCUUCUGUCGCUGGCGCGACUGCCAGUGCGCCAACUGCCUGCUGGUGGUGGAGCGGCAGCGCGUCAUGGCCGCCCAGGUGGCGCUCCGGAGGCAGCAGGCCACCGAGGACAAGAAGGGGCUUUCCGGGAAACAGAAUAAUUUCGAGCGCAAAGCUGUGUACCAGAGGCAAGUCAGAGCCCCCAGUUUGCUGGCCAAAAGCAUUUUAGAAGUUCUCCUUGGAUUAUUCUACAGCUAUUAUGUGUACAUAAUGAACCAUCUUUAGAAAAUAAAAGUGACAUCAGCUCUAGGUAUAGAUAUAUUUUUUAAUAAUGAAAAAAGAUGACAUGGAUAAUAAUAAAACAUUGAUUGAUACAAGAUAAAUAGUCUUGUCUCUUAAUGCGUAGGGGGCCUGGGAAGAAUAUUAAAAUUUUAAUCAAUAAAGUAUGUCUGUUGAAGCAAGCAAGCAAACAAAUCCAUAACAACCACAACAAGCAACAAGAACAAGAACAACAACAAGAAGAAGUUGCAGUAUGGAUAUCUUUCACCCUCCCAGGAAACUCUUUCAAACCUAAUCUGUACUUUUGCAUCUGUAUAAAAAUAUCAGUGAGAUGGAACUGUAAAUAAUUGUUCUGCUGAUCUGUAGUGUUGCUGUUACCUUCUGGGUUUCCACAUUUUUAUUCCGUAGAUGUUAAUCUCUUUCAUGUGCAAUCUUUGCUUCUUGUAGGCUAUCGCCCCAUUCCAGCGGAGACUUAUGUAGGAGGGACCUUCCCUCUACCUCCCCCAGUUAGUGACAGGAUGAGGAAAAGAAGAGCCUUUGCUGAUAAAGAGUUGGAGAACAUUAUGCUGGAGAGAGAAUAUAAAGAAAGGGAGAUGUUGGAAACUUCUCAAGCUGCUGCUCUGUUUCUGCCCAACCGCAUGGUGCCUGGACCUGACUACAAUUCCUACAAAAGUGCCUACAGCCCCAGCCCAGUGGAACCACCAAGCAAGGACUUCUGUAAUUUUUUGCCCACCUGCCUUGAUUUAACCAUGCAGUAUUCAGGGUCUGGGAAUAUGGAACUAAUUUCUUCUAAUGUCAGCGUGGCCACAACUUAUAGACAGUAUCCCUUGUCCUCAAGAUUUUUAGUUUGGCCCAAGUGUGGCCCCAUUAGCGACACCCUCCUCUACCAGCAAUGCCUGCUAAAUGCCACCACCUCAGUUCAAGCCCUGAAGCCUGGGGCCAGCUGGGACUUGAAGGGAGCACGAGUCCAGGAUGGACUCAGUGCAGAGCAGGACAUGAUGCCAUCGAAAUUGGAAGGUUCCCUGGUGCUGCCUCACACUCCUGAGAUCCAGACCACGAGAAGUGACCUUCAGGGUCAUCAGGCUGUCCCAGAGAGGUCCGCGUUCUCCCCACCCCGACGGAAUUUCUCUCCCAUUGUUGACACGGACUCCCUGGCAGCUCAAGGGCAUGUCUUAACGAAGAUCAGCAAAGAAAACACCAGGCACCCUCUGCCACUUAGACAUAAUCCAUUCCACUCAUUAUUCCAGCAAACACUUACUGACAAAUCGGGUCCUGAGUUGAAAACACCAUUUGUCAAAGAGGCCUUUGAAGAGACCCCUAAGAAACACAGAGAGUGUUUAGUUAAGGACAACCAGAAGUACACAUUUACAAUAGAUAGAUGUGCAAAAGACCUUUUUGUAGCCAAACAAGUUGGAACAAAACUCUCGGUGAAUGAACCACUGUCAUUUUCUGUUGAGUCUAUUCUUAAGAGGCCUUCAUCUGCCAUCACUCGUGUCUCUCAGUGAAAGGCUGCUUAAACAGAAAGCUGGAUUUUCUGCAGUCUUAGAGCAUUAUAGCCAUUUGCUACUUUUUUUAAAAGUUAAGAUGUUUGUGUAAAGAAAUUUCUAAUGUAAAGAUGAUGAUUUUGAAAAAUUUUAUAUAUUCCUAAUAUGCAUGUACUUUUUCUUAUCACAUAUAUUUAAACUUACAGAUGGAAAUUGCCCAAUGUGCAAAUUGUUAAGUACCACACUUUACACAGCAUUUCAAAAAGCAAUAAAAUUGACACUGUCUUCUCAAAGACCCAA